AUUCAUUGUUCUUCUUGCCUGCCUGGAAGUCUGCAGCUAAAAUUGUGUUAAGGAGUUUACUGCUGAAGCUGCUACAGAAACCAAUGUCUUUGUAUUUUCCUGCUAACGAAUACGGGGUGCUUUGCAUUCAGGAAUACAGAAAAAACAGCAAAGUGGAGUCAAGUACACGUAACAACUUCAUGGGCUUGAAGGAUCACCUAGGGCAUGACCUCGGCCACCUUUAUGUGGAGAGCACUGACCCACAGUUAAGUCCAGCUGUACCUUGGUCAACAGUAGAAAACCCAAGUAUGGAUACCGUUAAUGUGGGGAAGGAUGAAAAAGAGGCGUCUGAAGAGAAUGCAAGCUCUGGUGACUCUGAAGAAAACACAAAUUCUGAUCAUGAGUCAGAACAAUUGGGUAGCAUUUCAGUAGAGCCAGGCUUGAUAACUAAGACUCACAGACAGCUCUGCAGGUCUCCCUGUUUAGAGCCUCACAUACUCAAGCGCAAUGAAAUUUUGCAAGACUUUAAACCUGAAGAGUCCCAGACUACAUCCAAGGAAGCAAAGAAACCACCUGAUGUGGUGCGAGAAUACCAAACAAAACUGGAGUUUGCACUUAAGUUAGGUUAUUCUGAAGAACAGGUUCAGCUUGUACUAAACAAACUUGGUACUGAUGCUUUAAUCAAUGAUAUUUUGGGAGAACUUGUCAAACUUGGAAAUAAAAGUGAGGCUGAUCAAACGGUUAGUACAAUUAACACUAUAACACGGGAAACUUCUUCCCUGGAAUCUCAGAGGUCUGAAUCUCCAAUGCAAGAGAUUGUAACAGAUGAUGGUGAAAAUCUGAGACCAAUAGUUAUUGAUGGCAGCAAUGUGGCAAUGAGCCAUGGAAACAAAGAAGUAUUUUCCUGCAGAGGAAUAAAAUUGGCAGUGGAUUGGUUUUUGGAAAGAGGCCACAAAGACAUUACAGUUUUUGUUCCUGCUUGGAGGAAAGAGCAAUCCCGACCUGAUGCUCUCAUUACAGAUCAGGAAAUUUUACGUAAAUUAGAGAAGGAGAAAAUCCUGGUGUUCACGCCAUCCCGGCGAGUCCAGGGGAGGAGAGUGGUGUGCUAUGACGACAGGUUCAUCGUGAAGCUGGCUUUUGAGUCGGACGGUAUCAUUGUGUCCAAUGAUAACUACAGGGACUUGGCUAAUGAGAAGCCAGAAUGGAAGAAGUUCAUAGAUGAACGAUUAUUAAUGUAUUCAUUUGUCAAUGACAAGUUCAUGCCCCCUGAUGACCCUCUUGGCAGACAUGGCCCCAGUCUGGAUAAUUUUCUGAGGAAGAAACCUAUUGUUCCUGAACACAAAAAGCAGCCUUGUCCAUAUGGAAAGAAGUGUACCUAUGGACACAAGUGCAAAUAUUACCAUCCCGAAAGGGGCAGUCAGCCACAGCGGUCAGUGGCUGAUGAACUCCGUGCCAUGUCUAGAAAUACGGCAGCCAAAACUGCAAACGAAGGAGGACUGGUGAAAAGCAACAGUGUUCCUUGUAGCACCAAGGCUGAUAGCACUUCUGAUGUCAAACGAGGUGCUCCAAAGAGGCAAUCAGAUCCAAGCAUAAGGACACAAGUCUACCAAGACCUAGAAGAAAAGCUUCCCACCAAAAACAAAUUGGAAACCAGGUCUGUACCUUCCUUAGUUAGCAUCCCAGCUACUUCUACUGCAAAACCCCAAAGCACUACAUCUUUAAGCAAUGGCCUUCCAUCUGGAGUUCAUUUCCCACCUCAGGAUCAAAGACCACAGGGACAAUAUCCUUCAAUGAUGAUGGCAACCAAAAAUCAUGGAACGCCAAUGCCUUAUGAACAGUAUCCAAAAUGUGACUCACCUGUCGACAUCGGAUAUUAUUCCAUGUUGAAUGCAUACUCAAAUCUGAGUCUCUCAGGCCCACGAAGCCCUGAAAGGCGUUUCUCCUUAGACACAGAUUAUAGAAUAAGUUCCGUAGCUUCUGACUGCAGCAGUGAAGGGAGCAUGAGCUGUGGGAGCAGUGACUCCUACGUGGGUUACAAUGACCGGUCCUAUGUCAGCUCCCCCGACCCACAGCUAGAGGAGAAUUUGAAGUGUCAACACAUGCACCCUCACAGCCGCCUUAAUCCUCAACCGUUCCUGCAGAAUUUCCACGACCCCUUAACCAGAGGGCAAAGUUACAGUCACGAAGAACCAAAGUUCCAUCACAAGCCUCCUCUUCCGCACCUGGCUCUGCACCUGCCGCACUCCGCUGUGGGCGCCCGGUCCAGCUGUCCUGGCGACUACCCCUCUCCUCCAAGUUCAGCACACUCUAAGGCACCACACCUAGGGAGGUCCUUGGUGGCCACGAGAAUAGACAGCAUCUCUGACUCUCGACUUUAUGACAGUUCUCCUUCACGACAAAGAAAGCCUUAUUCCCGCCAGGAAGGCCUGGGAAGCUGGGAGAGGCCAGGCUAUGGGAUCGACGCCUAUGGGUACCGGCAGACUUAUUCCUUGCCCGAUAACUCCACACAGCCGUGUUAUGAGCAGUUCACCUUCCAGAGCCUCCCUGAGCAACAGGAGCCAGCCUGGCGGAUCCCAUACUGUGGAAUGCCGCAAGAUCCCCCGAGGUAUCAAGACAACCGAGAAAAGAUUUAUAUCAAUUUGUGCAACAUCUUCCCCCCUGACCUUGUGAGAAUUGUCAUGAAAAGGAAUCCUCACAUGACAGACGCCCAGCAGCUCGCCGCAGCCAUUUUAGUGGAGAAAUCCCAGCUGGGUUAUUGAAAGAUGAUGCAUCUUUGUGGUGUUUAGUAGUUUUUUGUUCAGCUCAAAUGCUGAGGGAGGUUUGCUACAAUAGCACAUGUGAUCUCCUUCUCAGCAAGGAGGUUAUAUAGUAUCCAUUUAUGUGAAAUACUGUAUCAUGGAAUCUGUAUGUAUAGCCCCACAUGGUGGAAGUAUCACGGGAUUGCUUUACAUUUAAACUUUUUUUUUUUAACAUUUCCUUUUUAAAGCUAUAUCCUUGGCUGGAAAUUUUUCCAGUUUGAUUUAAUAGAUGUAUCUGUGAUCUUUGAUAUUAAUCUUUGGUGCAUCAGGGGUUUAUAUGCAGCACUUUUUAUCCUUGUUUUGUGUUUUAUUAACUUGGUGUUUGUCUAUCAAUUGCAAGCAAUUACAAUACCUUCAGAAUGUGGGACAUUUGACUAGACCUAGCAAACUGUUUUUUCGAGCCAAGCUUAGUUAGACUCUUUUACAGCUUUUUAAGUUAUUUUUAUUUGGGGAAAGUGGGCUUCUUUGUGCUAUAAUCAUUAUUUAUAGAAACAAAGUUAUACUACAGCACUGACUUUAUAUUUUAAACAGAAUGUAAGUUACCAGUUUUAUGUUGAAAUGUGUUACAGUAUAUAUAUAUUAGAAUGAUUUACAAUAUGGCACUUUUCGAUGUGUUAUUUUUGUUUGGAUUUUUUUUUCUGUUAAGAAAUUAGUUAAUUUAAUAUGGUCAAUUUAAAAGAAAGCAGAUGCAAUCAAUGGAAAAAUGUUUCCAUUUUUUAAAAAUGAAUAAGGCAAAAGCUGUAACUGUUACAGGUUAGAGCUUUGUUAUCCAGCUAUGAUGUGCUUCUUGACAGUAGAAGUGGAAUUGAAUUCCUAGAUUUCCAUUAACCUGUAUUUUUAAUAUGUCUGUCUUUUUGUUUUGGGGCACAACAAUACUGGAUAAAAUAACCCUUUCACAGCACUUGCCUGUUUUUAAUGAAUCUAAUUAUUCACAAUGCAACUUUUAUAUUUAACAUACUCUUUAGCUUUCCUGCUAUUUAUCAAGGCUGGCCUGAGGUGGGUUUAUGUGUUGAGGUUAUGCAACAUUUCUUGAUACUGCACUAUAGAGAAAUGGUGAUGGAGGAGUUGUAAAUGGUAACUUAAAAUUUUUGUAAGAUAUUGUAUAUUUUCCAUUUUCCUGAAGGUAGUUUUCUUGGGGGGGCCUGUUAUAUUAUUAAGGCCAGACUCUUGCCACAAAUAGUGUAGUUUUAGAUACAGACUAAGGUCUGUUCUAGUAUUAGUAAGGGAUAUUUCUGGUUUCAAAGUCAUGGGUUUUGCUAGUGGUGAAUACAUUUCUGCGGAGUAGAAGAUAGAUUUUGCAGUCAGUGGCAGACAGUUGUGUGAUUGACAUCACUUGACUGUUGCGUCCAGGUUUUGAAUUGUACUUCACGUAACAGAUGCAUUCAGAUCUUUUUCUGUAGUCUGCUUAGAUGCCCUGGCUAUUCUGAUUAUCCUACAUGCUACAGUUUGAAGUGAAGCCCUGAAAAACCAGAAAGUACCUUUUACUGUUGAUACAAAUUGUAUCUUUUUAACUAUAAGAACUAUUUUGAUUUGUAGAUCUAGUUAAAACACAAGUAUGUAACUAUGAUUAGACUUUUGGGCAACAUUUUAUCCCUUAUUUAAAUACAAAUUUUUAAAGUAAAAUUGAGGUCUAGAAUAGAUUAGAAAAUAAAAAUAACAAUUUAGAUAAAUAGAAAUGUCUGUCUUAGUUUUAUAUAAUAUAUUAAAACACAGUAAAUAAAUUUAUUGGCAUUUUCUUUCUCCUAAAACUUACCUAGUGUGAACUUAAAAUAAAGGUAAAAUGCUGCCUGAAAAUAAUGUCCAAGCACCUUUGACUAGGAUAACAUUUUCACUACUUGUGUGACACUGUGUGUUGCACGAAGUAGGAUUUGGGUAUACAGUAAAUGCUUCUAAAAGGCAUUGUGCAUAUUGACAUAACCAAUAAUCUGAACCGUGUUCAGCAAACUUAAUUCAGGAAAGUGGUAUUCUACACAAUUAUUGCUGUUGUGUUUGAAAUGAGUGUGGCACUCAUCUGUAUCCAGAAAUAAUAUGGGUGAGGCCACACAACCCAUUCUGAGUGGUGUCUGUCUGAAAGCAACCCUACUCGCAUGUGAAAUUGUUCUCCUUGAUUUGGUCACUAUAAAGCAAGUUUAAAUGUAGAGGCUAACUCAGUGCCAAAAACAGGGUUACAAAUGUGUAGUAUCUUUUAUUUUAGUCAUAUUCUAAGACUUCUUUUUAGUAUGAAAUCACUUUUAAAUUAUACAUGUAGGUUUUGCUUCCAUUUUCUUCAUUUUACCAUUUUAAUUAUUUGAACAUUCGCCAAAUUUUACAUUUAUUUAAAUGAGAUCUUAGGUGAGAUGUGUGUGACACUUUGAAUUUGACCUUCUUGUGUUAUUAGCUGACUAUUUGUCAUUGCCUCAUGGAUUUUAAAUUAUGGGAAAAUAGUGUAGCCAGCUGCCACCUCUACUGAAGUGAGUAGCUCUGAACUACCCACACUAAAUCCUUCAGUGUAAUUAAUUAUGAGUUUAAAAAUAGCAGUUUUCUUAUGUGAAGAGGACAGUUUGUCCCCUUUUUUUGAAGCACCGAUGUUGCGUUCAGAGCUGUAGAAUGAGAUAAUUGGCAGACUUUAGGUACAGCAAAUUCUUACUUAUCUAAAGCAAUAAGUCAAAGGAGUCCAUCAUUAAAUUAAAUCCAUAGCUGAUCACAAGCCUUCAUUUUAGCCAAAACUUUCUCUCUAACCAAAUCUUUUACCAGACUUGCUAAUAAAUAACCAGAGAGAUGUGUUAAUAAGUGAAGUUGCCAGAAAUGGUCAACUGAUCGGAAAAAAAAGGAUUCAGACUGGAGUAUUUUGCCCCUGAAUAAUUGACAGUUGACUGUGCUUUACACAGUAACUAGCCAGUCUGUUGUCUCUGUGUCUUAGUCCAGAGGGAAUAGUACCCAAUUGGCCAAAUACUGGCCCUUAGUAUCUCCUCCUUUCUUGCAUGGGAUACAGACGUUUUCAGUCUUGUUUUUAUGAUCUCUCUCUAUAUCCUGAUAAGAGUUUGUCAUUGACUUACACAUUUGGAAGAAAUGCACACCAGUGUAAUAUAUUUGAUACUGGUGGAAACUUGAACUUUGUGUUUUUAUGAAAAUUCAUUUAUGAGAAUAUGUAAUAUAACUGAAGAGUAUUUUAUGUAUAUCUAUAUACACAAAUAUGUAUUUGUUAUGAGGUAUUAAAAACAGGGGUUGGGGGGAGUGCUUCUGAUGGCUAACUUUUCUCUAAUUAAACUAUGUUUCUUUGAGUUGUGAACGACCGAGUCUGGGGUCUGGACGGCCAAUGAUAAGAUUUAGAACCACUUGGAUGGAAAGCAGUUCUUCACUGGUUUUAUUCUUGGUAUUUUCAAAGAAUUAUUUUGAUAUUUUUAAUAGAAUGUGUAAUUUUAAAAUACACAAAAAACUUAAAGUAGUAUUGAUUAUACAAAUAAUUAUUUAACAUGUCUUAUGGAUGUAUCUAUAUGUAUAUAGACAGUAAUAUAUUUAUAAAACAAAUAUACUUUGCUUAUGUUAUAGCUCUUAGUUUGUGACAGGUGGGAGGAUGGCUCUGGGUGUGUGUGUGUGUGUGUGUGUGUGUGUGUGUGUGUGUGUGUUUUGAAAACUCUCAAGCUGUUUUCCCUCUGAUUUACAAUGGUAUUUACUUUAAAGUAUGUUUGGUUUUCAUUAUUCUUUUUGCUCUCCAACUUCCUUAUUCAAGAUAAAAUAAGACAUACAGUUUUCUGGCCAUUCUGUUGGUGUGUGGUGCACCCAUUUUAUUGUCAUCUAACUCCUGGAGAAUUCCCACGUGACCUGAAAUCAAACAGAUUCUGGCUGGACAUAUGCUUAUGUUCCAAAUAUAUUAAAGAUGUUAAUUCAGCUAACAGUUAAGUUUCCAAGGUAUACACCAACAAAUAAAAUGAGGUAUUAAAAAGAGAUGGAUUACACACAUGCAUUAGAAUAAGAGAAAACAGUAGUGUUAAUAAAAGUAAAGAAACAUACACUAUCUUAGCCCCCUAGGGCAGGGGUUGACUUUUUCUGUAAAGGAUCAGAUAGUAAAUAAUACAGGAAUCAUAUGGACUUCAAAUGCCAUUGUAAAAACUACUCAGCUCUGCCUUUAGAGCAUAAGAACAGCCACAGAUAACAUGUAAAUUAGUGUGGCUGUGUUCCAAUAAAACUUUAUUUACAGAAACGGGAAGCCGGUCAGAUUGGGCCUGUGGGCCAUAAUUUGCUGAUCUCAAGCAGUAAAUCCUGGUAUAUGUUAAUAGAAGAAAUCAUAAUUGCAUUUCAGUUGACAUUAAAAGAAAAUCUGGUAGUUUUUGAUGUCCUUCAAAAGAGGAUUGUUAGACAUUGAUGUUAAAGCAUCUUAAUUCAUUUGAGUUUUCUUACCUGUUUACACCCAUUAUUUAUUAGAGAUAUUUCUUGUGUUUAACCACAAAAAAAAGCACUCUGUUAAAAUGUUUUAAUAUGUAUUGAAUUUCUUUCAUAAACUUUUCAUUUCUGUUGAUAAAUGGGAAUCCCUUACCAACCUUUUGUUUUUUAAAAGUCUCAUAGACCAAAAAAAAUCUGUUGCAGCAUUUAAUUAGCCACAGAUACAUUUUGGCUGCAUUUACCAGUUACAUUUUUCCAUUGGUUUUGGCUUCUAAUAAAUAACAUAUCUGCCAUUCUUUAAAAAUGAUUUUAAAGAAGAUAAAUAUAUUGUAAUUUCACAUGCUAUAGCUUUAUUCUGUAAGAUUAAAAAUUGUGACUAGUAUAAUUGUAGCUAUAAUGUGAGUGGCAUGUUACAAUGUAACUCUUUAUGAGAAAUAAAAUGUAUCUCUGCUUUGUCUGUCCAGAUCUUUAGGAUUUUUAGAUGCCUUGGGACUGUCCUUGGUGAAUGAUAUUCUUCAUAUGAUCAUAUGUAAUUUUGAAUUCGUUGGAAGUACACGCUGCUGAGCAUGUUUAUUCACAGUGCUUUAUACCGGGUGUUGCAUCAGUAAUCAUUUUCAUAAGAACAUUUAAACAGCAUGAACAUCAUCAUCCACUUAAAUAGUUAAACUUUCUUUUAAAAUUGGAAUGCAACUGUAGGUUUUAACAAUGUUUAUUGUUUUUUAAGUGGUUACUUUGUUUUUCCUUAAUACUUUCUGUUAACUUAAUUAUUACUCCUGUUGCAGUGUUACUGUUAUGUAUUAGAAGUGGCUUUUCCCCCUAAGAUCCUUAGUCUUUUAAAGACAAUUUAAGGUAUUGGCCAUUUGGCAGUAGAAAAUGUGCAUGUUUUAACUUGGUUUUAUAAAAUCUGUAAUGUUUCACUUCUUGAACCAUGUACCAAAUUUGCCAAUUUUCUGUCCAAGUGUUUCAGAUGAAUAACAAAACGCUGUUCAUUGAAGCUUUCGCCACCUUUCUUAAAGCAGCGUAUGUUCCAAGGGAAAAAGGCAUUGAAAAGCAAUCGUUUGUUUUUAUGAAGAAUAGGUGUUCAGAUUCCUUCAGUUUUUUUGAAAUUAGAAAUUUCUUACCUUAUGUGAAAUAUUCACAAACGUGCACACUUCUGCAGAGACAAAGCAUUUCACUGCACGUGUACCAGGUUAUUGAUUUUAUCUUUUCCUUUCAGGGUUUUGUCCUCCCAAACCAGAGUCAUAUGCUGCUAGUAGAAUUUUUUAUUUGAUCCUGCGAACUUUUCUUAUAGGAAAAGUAAGGCAAAGGAUGUGUAGUGCAACCAUCUGAUAAACUAGUGUGAUUGUAUUUAUCCUCUGUUCUGUGUAUUUCUGUAAUGGAAUCUUUACAAUUCCCAAAACGGUAUUUUAGACCUACUGGAAAUCUGUAUCGAAACAGCUAUGUGAUUCUGCCACUGAGAAAAAAAAAAUUUUUAAUUCGUUUUUCUUAUGCUGGUUUGUUUUUCUUUAAUGAAGAAAUUGAUCUCAUAUGGCAUCAUAGAUGCUAAAUAAAUAAAAGCAUCAUACUUCUCUAGUUUGCCUGCAUUCAGUGGCUAACAUUAUGAGCAUUGUGUAAGAUAAACACAUGGUCAGUAUCAAUGUAAAUGUUAGAGCCAUGAUUAAUUCCUAUGAAAAUUGAAAUUAAAUGUCAAAGACAACUAGACAUAA